GCCUGUCUCUUUAAAUGCCACGGGCUGCGCUCCCGCCCGGGAGCCCGGAGCCGGAUCUACAAUCCCGUCCCUCCAGCUCCGGUGCUUGUUGCUCGCCCGGCCCAAGCGGGAGCUGUUGCCGCCAGGCUGCGAGGCUGCCGUCCUCUCCUCCUCGCGCCCCACCUCCCCCGAGAGCUGGCUGAGGAGGGGCAGCAGCCCCAGCUGGCGGGAGGAAGCGCGGUGUGAACAGGGAUUGCCCCCCGCCUUCAAGUAUCGGGGCGCUACGCAGCCGCGGGGGAAAGACAUGCCCCUAGUCUGCCCGCUGCGCUGCCCUCUGCCCAGCCUCGCUGCCGCCCGCGCCGGGAGAGGAGGGACUGCCGAGCCUACACCUUCAAACUCGCCCUAGAAGUCUCGGGGCGCGGCAGGGAGCCCUUCCCCAGGCCCCACGGCCUUCACCUCUCCGCGGGUGAGUUUGUGCAGGUAGCCUCAGCCCCUGUCCGGGGACCUGUGCAAAUGACCCUGGAGUUGGUUUCGCUUUCUCCCCUUGCGGCGGUGUGAACGUGUGUCCGCAGCGUGAUGGGCAACCAGGUGGAGAAAUUGACCCACCUAAGUUACAAGGAAGUUCCCACGGCCGACCCGACUGGCGUGGACCGGGACGACGGGCCCCGCAUUGGGGUCUCCUACAUUUUCUCCAAUGACGAUGAGGACGUGGAGCCGCAGCCGCCGCCUCAGGGGCCAGAUGGCGGCGGCUUGCCCGACGGUGGGGACGGGCCGCCGCCGCCCCAGCCGCAGCCCUACGAUCCGCGGCUGCACGAGGUGGAAUGCUCCGUGUUCUACCGGGACGAAUGCAUCUACCAGAAGAGCUUCGCGCCGGGCUCGGCGGCGCUGAGUACCUACACGCCCGAGAACCUGCUCAACAAGUGCAAGCCGGGCGAUCUGGUGGAGUUCGUGUCGCAGGCUCAGUACCCGCACUGGGCCGUAUAUGUGGGUAACUUCCAGGUGGUGCACCUGCACCGGCUGGAGGUGAUUAACAGCUUCCUGACUGACGCCAGCCAGGGCCGUCGCGGCCGCGUGGUCAACGAUCUGUACCGCUACAAGCCGCUAAGCUCCAGCGCCGUGGUGCGCAACGCGCUGGCGCACGUGGGUGCCAAGGAGCGCGAGCUGAGCUGGCGCAACUCGGAGAGUUUCGCCGCCUGGUGCCGCUACGGCAAGCGCGAGUUCAAGAUCGGCGGCGAGCUGCGCAUCGGCAAGCAGCCCUACCGGCUGCAGAUUCAGCUGUCGGCGCAGCGCAGCCACACGCUCGAGUUCCAGAGUCUAGAGGACCUGAUCAUGGAGAAGCGACGCAACGACCAGAUCGGGCGCGCGGCCGUGCUGCAGGAGCUCGCCACGCACCUGCACCCGGCGGAGCCGGAGGAGGGCGACAGCAACGUGGCGCGGACUACGCCGCCUCCCGGGCGCCCCCCUGCGCCCAGCUCCGAGGAGGAGGACGGAGAGGCAGUGGCACACUGAUGGGCGAGCUGAGCGCAGAGCUGCGAAGGGGAACUGUUUGCAGUAGCAGCCGCUGCUCCCUUUCUCCCUCUCUUCCUCCCUCUUUUGCCACUGUCUGGGCCCCAUCUGGGAUUCCUGGGCCCUUUGGAAAAGAGUUGGUGAAAUGCGCAGCCGGCUGUGGACGGGGGAGGAGGAAGGGGACAGAGGGAGCAGGUAGGAAACACUUUAGUUGGGGGUGGGGGGCGUCUCCCUCUGGCCCCCUGUCUGUCUUCCUCUCCGCGGUGGAGCAAACUGUGGACUUGCCUGGCACUUAAACCUUGGUAGAUCUGGGUUUAUAAUCGGCCAUUCUUAAGCACGUGGGGUUGGGGGAAAGUUCGGAGUACCCAUUCCUGCCGUUGCUUCCUAUCCUGGGCUUGGAAGAAUCCUGGUAGAAAGGCCAGAGUGGGUUUGUGGAGUCGCCACUGCGGGACCAGCACGAAAGCUGCUUGUCUGCUUUGGCGGAGCUGAGCUGUGUAUGGGAUCCAGGAGGCUGGGGUGAUUUAUUUUAUGGGAUUCCUGGAGCGCAGGGCUGGUGAAUCCAUGACAAGGUCCGGGAGCAGCAGACCAAAACCACAGCAGCCUCCUAUUAAGUGUAACAAAUAGUUAAGCAAACUCGGGCUACAAACAAAGACUUUGCUACCUCCCUCCUCCACAACCCCCAAGUAAUUAGCCUUCUGGAGCUGGCUCUUAGCUGAGGCUCCUGCUACCUCCUGCUCCACCCGCCCCUUCCUAGGUUACAAGUAAAUCAUUGUCAAGGGCCAGCCAGGGGAAGGUUUCAAUUAAGGUUCUGUUCUGCUGCCUUUGUUUCUCCCCUGCUGUUGUAGGCACUUACAGCUGCGUUGUUAUGAAAGGAGGGAAUAGCCCUUUGUGUCUUUGAUCUAAUUAAACCUGCUUGGCUGUGUUUAUCCGCAGGGCAGGUCACAGAUAGGGUUGGCUGUGCCACUCCAUAAAGUAUCUAUUGUGGAAGCAGCCAAAAAGGGCUGCUGUGGCAGGAAUUGGUUAAUUUCUCCUUCCACUUCCCUUCCUGAAUAGUGAAGGGAGCCCUUUUAAAACAAGGCUUUGGUGGUAAUCCUGUGAUUUUUUUUUCUCCCCCAUCCCCUCACUGGCCCAUCCCUCUCACCCUCACUUUUGUUCUGCUGGUGGGUAAAAUCUUAGGCUGAACACAUAUUUCAAUGGUAAGAUACUUAUUUUGCUAUCCACACUUGAUGCAAUUGAAUUCAAGGUGCAAAGUCUUGUACUGAAGCAGUCUCCUUGUUGCUUGGAGAACACCUCCUUCAGAGCCCUUUGUUAAAUAAGAGGGGCGACGUUGAUCAUAGAUGCCACCUGGUUAGCACCGAAUCUGACUUUGGUGACAGUCCUAAAGCACAGUUGGUGAUUGUGAGAUCUGUUAGCGGCAGGCUGAGCAGAUACUACUUGGUUUUGCUUGGUAUGAGAUACUACUGUUUGCUUAGUAUGAGAUUUUUUCCAGCCUGUCUCUUAAACUCCUGUGACAUCUUCAAUGAUAUGUGCCCUCAGUUGCAGCAUAGCUUCUCUGCUGCCUAUUGCCAUUGCUGUCUCAAAAGUUGAGUGAAUUUUGAGGCGUCUUUUUUUUUUUUUCCUCUCUUGGGAGUCGUUGUAAACUACUGUGUACAAGUCAUUUUGUGAUAUGAUUCUGAACAGUUGGAAUAGAAUCAUAGUUAAGUGGUACAGCCAUGGCUAUCGUCAGGCCUGUUGCCUGGAGAUCUCUAAGUUAAGGCAACAAGACUUAAAGAAUUUUCUAAUACACUUGUUUCACACAUGGACGUUGAGGCCAUAGUCUUUAAAAGCUUGGACCUUUGUAGCACCUCAACAUGAAAGGGCAUUAGCUAUGUUUCCUGUUUUUACAGUGAUCACCAAACAGAUCUUGCCACUUUGAUUGUUAAAAAUGAACCACAUUCUAGCCCUGGUCUGGGACUUUGGAGGGAGAUGAAUUUCUUGUUGGAAAUGUAAAUCUAGUGUCCAUAUUUAAUACUCUCACAGCUUUGUGUUUAUUCUCUUUGCUCAUGGAAUAGCAGAACAAGAUAAACAUGGGUUAAGACAUUUAGGAGAACCUGCUGUAUCUAACCCAGUUGGAUUUUCUUUCAUGCUUAACACAGUAGUGAAAAUAGAAGGUAGGCCGGGCACAGUGGCUCAUGCCUGUAAUCCCAGCACUUUGGGAGGCUGAGGCAGGUAGAUCACCUGAAGUUAGGAGUUCGAGACCAGCCUGGCCAACAUGGCGAAACCCUGUCUCUACCACAAAUACAGAAAAUUAGCUGGGCGUGGUGGCAGGCGCCUGUAAUGCCUGCUACUUGGGAGCCUGAGGCAGAAGAAUUGCUUGAAGCUGGGAAGCAGAGGUUGCAGUGAGCCGAGAUCGCACCACUGCACUCCAGCCUGGGCAGCAGAGCAAGUAGUAAUAACCACCGUGUAGACAAGUGGGAGGGAAGAAUAGAAUGGCACUGUCCAGCUCUGGGCUAGCCAGAUCAACUCCCCCACCCGUCUUCUUCCUCUGUCCCAGAAUGGAAAAUGAUGUAUGGUCAGUCACGCUGAAGUAUAGCAGCGACUGUGUUAAGAGAGAGCAGUGACUCUCUCUUCUAGAGAAGAGGUUUUCAAUAACAGGGCUUGGAAAUGAACUAGAAUAGGAAAUAGAUCUUUUCAGAUGCUGCUUUCCCAUGUAAUACAAGCGUUUCUACAGGGUACCAGAGGUGUGAAAUAUGUGACACUUAAGAACAGUGAUUUUUAUUGGGAAUUUUCUUAGGGUUAUUACACUUAAAGCAACAACCAACUAGUAACAGCUCCAGGAAAGGGGAAUGAAUCAACUCUUGGUUCUUUCCUGAAGACGGCAGUGUUGUGGAUAAGUGAGUUUUUAAUGCCCUGGCAGUGGCUACAUUUGACACUUUAGAAAAAAUAAACAUAUUUAAUAAUUUUUGUUUCUCCUUAGGAAUAAGACUGUAGAACUGUUUUGUACUGUGAAUUACGGAUGCUCUUUGAAGGAAAGAAAUAUCGAUUCUAAUGUUCUUCAGAAGUUCUGGCAGGGAUAAGCAGGACAUCGACUGGAACGUAUGCUAAAUGAAAGCAGACAAAUUUCUAUUUUCUUACCUGAGCAAAUAUUUUAUUGAAACUGCUUAUGUAUGUCAAAGGAGCCCACAACUUCAGCUACACAACUUUUUGUAUUGAAAGAACUCAUACUUUUUGUAGCUUUUAUUUCACAUUUAAUUUAAAGUGACUUUUAGCACUAAAAUGCCUAGAAGAUUUUACUCCAGACCUAUAAGGAAAUGUUUAGUUUUUAUGAAAAAUGACAAGUCGAUGGUUAAACUUCUCAUGUCUUUGGUGCUUUGGCCCUAAUAGCACUGGACAACACCACGACCACAUGGAAACAUAUUUUUGGAAGCAAAACUUUAAUUUUAUAUAACGUAUGCUAUGGAGAGCUAAGACAAUUUAAGGACUACUUGUUUUCUAUUUUUUUUCUUAAUAAAAUGGAAUCCACUGUGUUGAAGACUCUUGAUAUCAUGUGCUUGUCUAACCAUUUUUUGUUUUAUAAAUUAGAAUAAAAUAUAGUUGUGAUAAUGGUCAUCGAAUGGAUUUGUUUGGAAAGCUACAUCUUAUUUGUGAAAUGUUUUUUAAAUCAGAGUAACUAUCAACUGAUUCAGCUUUUUGUUGUUUUGUUCUUGGCUAUAAUACUUGUGACUCAUGAAGAAUUAUGUUGACAAACAGGAUAAAUUCCACAUGCAUUUUAUUUCCCAGUGAGUUGUAUAAACUUUAUUUUUGUUGAAGGUUGUAUGUUAAAUCAAUGUUACAUUCUUAUAUCACUUCUUGAGAAGGAAGUUCCGAUUUGAAAUUGUAUCAUUUCCUUCAAAAUGAAGGGCAGUGCUUAGUUAAAUAAAAGAUUGAUGAUAUCUUUUAAGCCAUUUCCUCUUCACUAUGUCUUAUUAAAAUAAAACCUGUCAAGUUCUUUUCAAAAGAUGCUAUGAGCGUUUCCAAUAAACCAUCUAUUAGAGUUCA